AGUCUCCGCGCUGCUGAGGCGCGCCCGGCCGCUCCCACGGCCUCCCCUCCGCCCUGCGGUCCCGCCGCCUCCGGGGCCUCCUGGGACCCUGGCCCUCGCCGGGCAGGACGCCGCCAGCGCUGAAGGCGCAGCCCGGAGGCCGCGCGGGUGAGUCGGUGCGCAGCCCCAGCGGCUCCAGAGGAGCGGGUGCGGGGAGGGCGAGCGGACCAAGUCGGCCGCGUUCCCACCUUGCGCGCAGCCGGGAGACCAGCAGGCCCAGCCUCUAGGGAGGAGGGCAGGGGAGCUGGGGGCCGCCCCCCGCAUUCUCGCAGGCACCUGUCCCUAGGCCGGGGUCCGCUGGCUCGAAGCACUGACCCGCCCCGGACCUAGGGGGACGGAGGCAGCGGUGACAUUUGCCCAGGAAGGGCGGCAGUGGGUAAACUCCACUCCAGGGCACGGGUCUGGGCGCAGGUUGAGGCCUGGGGUUGAAUCUGCUUCUGCUAGAGGCCAGUGUUCUCAGGGAGGCCCAUAACCCGACUGGGUCUCAGUUCCCCCUGGUAUGAAACAGCAACAGGGCAAGAGGAGGAAACCAUGCCACGCUGCAAAGCUCUGAGCACGAAGCCGAGAAGAAUCUCGGCUCCCGGCCUCGGGGGCUGCACUUCGGGCCAGGCCUGCACUCCCAGGAUAAGAGGAUGGCCUCCUGCCCCAGGGGUGGCAUGGGGGCGCGCAAAAAGCAAAGGUGACCCUGCCAGGGAGCACCCAGCGCUCCGGUUGGUGGUCAUGGGGUCUUUGCGUGGGACUCACAGUGUGGCCGGGAAAGUUCUGUAAUGAGGACAUUUCUCAUCAUUCCUUCUUCUCAAAAGUCAUUCGUCAGCCCCAGACACCUUUGCCUCGGAAAACUGAGAACUACUUUCAAAAUCGUCAACACCCCCAUCUCCUGCUACAGAGCGGAGUCCCCACUUUGCAGAGGCGCACUGCAAGGUCGCGGGUGGUUAAAUGGUGCGCCCUCCUUGAUGAAGAUGCCUUGUUCUCUUUCACUCUCUAUGUGUGUUUAAUGUUGUGUGUUGCGUUCUCUGUGAAGCGAAGGAUAAACACGGGCCCUUUCAGGCAACCGAAGGAAGAAGGCGGCCAGCAUCAGAUCUUCCCGUGCUUCAAGGUGGAGCACCCUGCAGGGCUUACUGCAGCGCUCAGGGUCAAAGUGAGGAUGCAGUGCGGCACCAAAAGGCAAAUGGACUCUGGAGAGCCACUCUCACCUUGUACCCCUGGAGUAGACCCCGAGGACUGGAGGACUGGAACAAGAUCUUAGUCCUGAGGGCGGGAGAAGCAGCCUUUGGUGGUUGCACAGGGGCCCGGCUUUUCCCGAAGUCUUAAAGCCUGCUCCAAAUGCCAGAUUCAGACAAAGGGGCCGAACCUUGGGCCCGCCGCCUUCUCCCAUAAGCGGCAACCCAGCAGCUUUGCCAGGAAGUUUACAUGUGAAGGUACGGACCUUUCUUGGAAUGAGCCACACCUGAUGGCCCUGCCACUCCGGACGGCGCUCGUUCACGGCUGUCCCUGGAGCAGACACGGUUCUGCGCACACACCUGGGCGCCGGAGAAACAGGGCACCCAAAGCGGGCCCAGGCCCUCGGACUCAGCGAGCUGGACACGUGUCCCCAUCACCCGCGGCUGGCGGGAGCAGUGUUUCUACUCCCUUCCCUCCCCUCCUCCCGCCCCGCAGAUGUGCUGUCUUUCCCGGCCUCCCCCCGCGCCCAGCACAGUGGUUUCUGCUUGGCUGUUCCCCUGUCUCUGAGAUGGUCUCUCCCUGCUGCUUGCCCUACACAUUCUCCCACACAGGCGCGCGGGAUGCCCCUGUCGGCGUGGUUGUCAAUGCCUGCUCCCCUGCCCCCCAGUCCAAUCUCCACGACUCUGGGCCCUGUCGCUUCAUCCUAAAGCCUUCCGCUCACGAGCCCUCCCGACGACCGACCCCCAGGAGGCUACUGGAGAUGCAGGAUUUGGACCCGUGCUGGACCCGCACCCGGACAGAUCCCUCUGAAUGAAUGAAUGAAUUAAUGAGCAGGCUGCAUCCUGAUUAGGUUAAGCCCUGAGAUAGGUACUUGUUUUAAAGCUGAGGUAUAAAUUGGGGUUCAGAGAGAUUGAGUGCUUUCACCAUGAACAAGUGACAGAGAGCAACGACUUGAACCGGGUUACCUGAUGCCACCGCUGGUCUUAACCUCCAUGUUAUUAGCGUAUUGGGUAAGUGAAACCGUGUGAGCCAAGAAGCUGGGGUGAGAAACAGCACGGAAUAGAGGAGAGGGCUGCAGAAAGGCGUGAUGUUUCUGGAGCACCGAAUUCUACUCACGAACACAGGAGUGGAGGCGGGAAGGGGACACUGGAAGCUAUGGAGGGCCUUGUCAGCCACAGUAAGGAAUGUGGACCUGGUCCUCAGGGUGGUGAGGGGAUGGCCCCCCAUCCAGAGGUUUCUCACAGGGGAGUGAUUCGGCCUGUCUCUGCCGCAGUCAGAAGGAAGGAUGCAGUGAGAGAGGGAAAGUGGAGAGGCGGAUGGCGGUGCAGUCUACUCCAGGUCAUGCUUCUUACCAUCUCCCUCAUUAUUCAUCCACAGAAAAUGAUUGCUGUUAUAUGACACACUGGUUAACAAAGGAGGGGGCUGUUUGCAAACAGAAACAACCAACCCAGGGCCUCCAGCCAUCCAAAGAUUCUGCACAGCCAGCCACCCCUAAGGCUAAGAAAUCCCAGAUGCAGAUCUGUGGAUCCAGCGUAGCAUCUGUAGCAGCUGGGACAUCAUUCCAGGUUUUGGGCCCGGUGUGUUGGCAACAACUGGAUCUGAAGAUGGCAGUCAGGGUGCUUUGGGGUGGUCUCAGCCUGCUCCGAGUGCUGUGGUGUCUCCUUCCGCAGACGGGCUAUGUGCACCCAGAUGAGUUCUUCCAGUCCCCUGAGGUGAUGGCAGAGGACAUCCUGGGCGUUCAGGCCGCGCGGCCCUGGGAGUUUUACCCCAGCAGCUCCUGCCGCUCGGUGCUCUUCCCCCUGCUGAUCUCUGGUUCCACCUUCUGGCUGCUCAGGCUCUGGGAGGAGCUGGGGCCGUGGCCUGGCCUGGUGAGCGGCUAUGCGCUGCUGGUGGGGCCUCGACUCCUCCUCACUGCCCUUUCCUUUGCUCUGGACGGGGCCGUGUACCACCUGGCCCCGCCGAUGGGGGCGGAUCGCUGGAACGCCCUGGCCCUGCUGUCUGGUUCCUACGUCACCCUGGUCUUCUACACAAGGACCUUCUCCAACACCAUUGAGGGACUCCUCUUCACGUGGCUGCUGGUGCUGGUAUCCUCCCAUGUAACGUGGGGCCCUACACGCAAGGAGCCGGCGCCGGGUCCACGGUGGCGCAGCUGGCUUCUUGGAGGCAUUGUGGCUGCUGGCUUCUUCAACCGGCCCACCUUUCUGGCCUUUGCUGUGGUCCCCCUCUACCUCUGGGGCACUCGUGGAGCCACAAACCCUGGUUUGAAGUCUCUGACCCGGGAGGCCCUGGUGCUGCUCCCUGGGGCAGCCCUCACAGCAGCGGUGUUUGUGGCCACGGACAGCUGGUAUUUCUCCAGCCCCGCUACAUCCAGGAACCUUGUCCUGACACCUGUCAACUUCUUGCACUACAACCUGAAUCCCCAAAACCUGGCGAGACAUGGCACGCACGCGCGGCUCACUCACCUGGCAGUCAACGGCUUCCUGCUCUUCGGGGUGCUGCAUGCCCAGGCCCUGCAGGCUGCGUGGCAACGGCUGCAAGUCGGCCUCCAGGCCUCUGCACAAAUGGGCCUCCUGAGGGCACUGGGUGCCCGGAGCCUGCUGUCCAGCCCCAGGUCCUAUCUCCUUCUCCUCUACUUCAUGCCUCUGGCCCUGCUAUCUGCCUUUAGCCACCAGGAGGCUCGGUUCCUGAUUCCCCUCCUGGUCCCCCUGGUCCUGCUUUGUAGUCCACAGACGCAGCCUGUGCCUUGGAAGGGCACUGUGGUCCUCUUCAACGCCCUCGGUGCCCUCCUCUUCGGCUGCCUGCAUCAGGGGGGCCUGGUGCCUGGCCUGGAGUACCUGGAGCAGGUGGUCCAUGCCCCUGUGCUCCCAAGCACACCCACCCACUACACACUCCUCUUCACUCACACCUACAUGCCCCCCCGGCACCUCCUACACCUCCCAGGCCUGGGGGCACCAGUGGAGGUGGUGGACAUGGGGGGGACUGAGGACUGGGCCCUGUGCCAAACCCUGAAAAGCUUCACCAGACAACCAGCCUGCCAAGUGGCUGGUGGGCCAUGGCUCUGCCGCCUCUUUGUGGUAACCCCUGGCACCACCAGGCGUGCCGUGGAGAAGUGCAGCUUCCCCUUCAAGAAUGAAACACUUUUAUUUCCCCAUCUGACCCUGGAGGAUCCACCAGCCCUGUCCUCCUUGCUGAGUGGGGCUUGGAGGGACCACCUCAGUCUUCACAUUGUGGAGCUGGGGGAAGAAACCUGACAAUAUGACAGAGCACCCACUGCCCAAGACUCAGCCAUAGAAGAUGCCGCCCCACCUUCUACUUGGGUAGCUGGGCUGGGACGCUGGGACAGGACCCCGUCCUCCUUCAUGACUCCCACUGCUGCCUCUCCUGGGCAUGGCUGUUAGCUGUUCUGCCUUCUGGGUGAGCUGGCACUCUUCUCCCUGAGACCAAAGAUUUGACCUGUCGGUCUUGAUGUCAAGGUCCCCAAAGACCAGGUUAAGUGACGACACCUGUCUGUUCCUGCCCUGUUGCUUCCAGCCACUGUGAUGUUUGAAAUAUGUGAUAGUACCUGGUUGUGAAAAAAGACAAUGAACUGCUAGUGACAUUCCUCAAUGACCUCUCCCAAACCUCCCAUGAUGCCUUACCCUUGCUGUCAUGACAACCCUCUGGCUUCCUAAGACCCAUCUGCCUAUCGAAAUAUGUGCAAGUCAGUGAGACGAAGUAUAGAGAACAGGUGGCCCAGAUCCAGGGGACCCAACUUCUGGCCCCUUGGUCUGUCACCUCCUCGCUGUGUGAUCUUGAGAAAGCUCCUUCCACUCACCCACCCCACUUCCCAGUCUGUUGGGAUCAGAGGAACUUUGAGGUGUCUGCCGGCUAACAUUGUGUCAUUCCUGGAGUCCACAGUACACGUCCCCUGCCUCAACAGGCACAGCUCUCACAAAGCUCUUCAAGCAUGGAAGUGGGAGUUGUGUUGUACUUCAUGGCACUCUGAUGCCUGCUGUCUCAGUGUUUGGUUAUUAUGCAAACAAGUAAUGUUUGAAAUAUAUAAUAGCACUGGA